CUACAUCUAGGACUGGCCUCCACUCAGCUAACUCCUCCUCCCCUCUCAUUUCUCCAAUUCAGCUCUAGUCCAGAGGAGAAAAGAAUAAUAAAUAUCACACUAAACACCAUGGAAUACUUCUCAAGUCACCAAAGAGAUGGAACUGGACAGAAUACUUCUGUCCAUAAGGCCCUUAGAAGCCCCCUAAGCGAAAUACCAAUGAGGACCUCCCCAGCAGCUGCUGUCUCUCCUGCCAGAGGCAUCUGGCUUAGAGCAGUGUGCAGUCGGCCAGCAAAGGGAUGACUCAAUGCUUGAACCUUCCUGACCUUCCCCUUACAGUGUGGAAAGAAGAAACCCUCUGGUGGCCUUGGCCCGGGAAUAUGGCGGUUUCAAGUGCAAUGCUGUACUGAAAUGGUACCAGAAGAAGACAGAAGGUUACAUGAUUUGAGGAAAUUGAAGUGCACUGCCUGGCACCCACUUUACUUCUGAAACAAUACAUGUGGUAACAGUAUUAAGUGCUCACUAUUUUGCAAACAUUGUUCAAGAACCCUAGGAAAGACAGUACAGAAUAAAUAGAAAGCAAAGUCUUUUUGUCCAAGAACUUAAAGCCCGUCAGUGUUGGGAACAUGCGAUUUGUGUGUGCAAUGGUGCAGGAGUCUGGUCGUGUCCAUCUCUGGGGUGCAGAGCUGCCUCUGAAGACUUGGCAAGACCUACCCAACAGUCGUUCACUGAGCAGAGACUGAGGAGCCUCCUGGGAUUGGGCUCAUCCUCAGGAAAAGCGGAGCCAGUCCCAAGCUUGAACCAGUGACAAGUCCUUGGAUGUCGGAGAGAAGUAGAACGUUGAGGUAUAAAAGUUUGGUCACGGGGACCCGAGCAAGAGGGGUCAUUGCUGUCCUCUGGGUCCUUGCCUUUGGCAUCGGAUUGACUCCAUUCCUGGGGUGGAACAGUAAAGACAGUGCCACCAACAACUGCACAGAACCCUGGGAUGGAACCACGAAUGAAAGCUGCUGCCUUGUGAAGUGUCUCUUUGAGAAUGUGGUCCCCAUGAGCUACAUGGUAUAUUUCAAUUUCUUUGGGUGUGUUCUGCCCCCACUGCUUAUAAUGCUGGUGAUCUACAUUAAGAUCUUCCUGGUGGCCUGCAGGCAGCUUCAGCGCACUGAGCUGAUGGACCACUCGAGGACCACCCUCCAGCGGGAGAUCCAUGCAGCCAAGUCACUGGCCAUGAUUGUGGGGAUUUUUGCCCUGUGCUGGUUACCUGUGCAUGCUGUUAACUGUGUCACUCUUUUCCAGCCAGCUCAGGGUAAAAAUAAGCCCAAGUGGGCAAUGAAUAUGGCCAUUCUUCUGUCACAUGCCAAUUCAGUUGUCAAUCCCAUUGUCUAUGCUUACCGGAACCGAGACUUCCGCUACACUUUUCACAAAAUUAUCUCCAGGUAUCUUCUCUGCCAAGCAGAUGUCAAGAGUGGGAAUGGUCAGGCUGGGGUACAGCCUGCUCUCGGUGUGGGCCUAUGAUCUAGGCUCUCGCCUCUUCCAGGAGAAGAUACAAAUCCACAAGAAACAAAGAGGACACGGCUGGUUUUCAUUGUGAAAGAUAGCUACACCUCACAAGGAAAUGGACUGCCUCUCUUGAGCACUUCCCUGGAGCUACCACGUAUCUAGCUAAUAUGUAUGUGUCAGUAGUAGGCUCCAAGGAUUGACAAAUAUAUUUAUGAUCUAUUCAGCUGCUUUUACUGUGUGGAUUAUGCCAACAGCUUGAAUGGAUUCUAACAGACUCUUUUGUUUUUAAAAGUCUGCCUUGUUUAUGGUGGAAAAUUACUGAAACUAUUUUACUGUGAAACAGUGUGAACUAUUAUAAUGCAAAUACUUUUUAACUUAGAGGCAAUGGAAAAAUAAAAGUUGACUGUACUAAAAAUGUA